GAAAAUGUAUAUUUUGUUGUGUUUGGAUGUAGUGUUUUUCAUAUAUAUGUUAGGUAUUGUUGGUUUAUAAUGUUUUCCAAGUCCUCUAUUUCCUUAUUGAUCUUCUCUCUAGUUGUUUUGACCAUUAUUGCAAGUGAGGUAUUGAUGUCUCCAACUAUUACUGUAGAACUAUCUAUUUCUCCCUUGAAUUUUGUUACUGUUUGCUUUAUAUAUUUUGGGGCUGUUGUUUGGUGCAUAUGUGUUUAUAAUUGUUAUAACUUUUUGCAGGGUUGACCCUUUUAUUAAUGUAUAAUGUCCUUUUUUGCCUCUACUAAUAAUUUUUGACUUAAAGUCUAUUUGCCAAUAUUAGUAUAGCUACUGUAACUCUCUUUUGGUUACUACUUGCAUGGAAUAUCAUUUUCCAUCUUCUUCUUCUAAAAGUAUUUGUGCCUUUGAAUCUAAAGUGAAUCUCUGUAUGUAGAAAAUAGUUGAAUCCUGUUUUUUCAAUUCAUUCUGCCUAUCUCUGCAUUUUAAUUGAAGAGUUCAAUUCAUUUACAUUUAAAGUAAUGACUGAUAUGUAAGGACCUACUUCUUGCAUUUUGCCAUUUCUUUUCUGUAUGUCUUAAACCUUUUCCCCUCAGUCCCUCCACUAUUCUAUUCUUUCAUGUAUAGUUUAUAUUUUUAAGUUUAGAUUCCUUUCUCAUUUCCUUUCCUGUAUUUUUAGUUAUUGUAUUGUUAUCCUCAGUGUUACAUUUAACCUCUUCAACUUAUAACAAGCUAUUUUGAAUUCACACUACCUUAGCUUCAAUAAUAUACAAACACUGUGCUCCAAUGUUGUUUCAUUCUGCUGCCUUUACGUUGUUGUAACAAACUACAUCUUUGUGCAUGUGUGCUCAUUAACAGAUUUAUAAUUAUUGUUUUACUCAUUUGUCUUUUAAAUCAUGUGGGAAAAAGGAGAAGUUGCAAAGCAAAAAUGCAAGAAUACUGGCUUUUGUAUUAAUCUAUGCAGUCAGAUUUACCUUCAUUCUUUGUUUCUUGGUAGGGAUUUGAGUUACUUUCUAGUGUGAUUUUAUUUCAGCCUGAAAGAUUCCCUUUAGUAUUUCUUACAGUACAAGUCUACUAGCAAUAAACUCUAUCUGCUUUUGUUUAUCUGCAAAUGUCUUAACUUCUCCUUCAUUUUUGAAGGAUAAUUUUUUCAGAUGUAGAAUUCUUGGUUGAUGGGUGUUUUUUUUUCUUUCAGCACCUUAAAUAUGUCAUCCCACUGCCUCCUGGCAAUCAUGGAUUCUUCUGAGAAAUUGGCUGUUGAUUUUAUUGAGCAUGACUUGUACAUGACUAGUUGCUUUCUCUUGUUGCAUUUGAGACUCUCUCCUUGUUUUCAUUUUUCUGGUUUGAUUAUAAUAUGUCUUGUUAUGGAUCUCUUUGUGAUCAUUCUUCUUGGAGUUCAUUGACUUUCUUGGAUGUAUAAAUUCAUGUCUUCUAUAAAGUUUGGGAAGUUUGGGGCCAUUAUUUUUUCAAAUAUUAUUUAUGCCCUUUUCUCUCUCUCUGCUCCUCCUUGGACUCCUAUUAUGCUUAUUUUUUGGUAUUUUUGAUGGUGUCCCACAAAUCUCUUAAGCACUGUACAUUUUUCUUCACUCUUUUCUUUUCUGAUCCUCAAACUGGAUAAUUUCAAUUGACCUAGCUUUGAAUUAGCUAUUUCUUACUUCUGCCUACACAGAGCUUCUGUUGAAAGCCUCUAGUGAAUUUUUUAUUUCAAUUAUUGUAUUUUUUCAGCUCCAGAAUCUCUACUUGGCUCCUUGUUAUUAUUUCUAUCUUUUAAAAAUAUUCUCUUUUCUUUAUAUAUCCUUUUCUUGAUUUCCUUUAGUUCUUUGUCCAUUGUUUCCUUUAGCUUUUUGAGCAUAUUUAAGAUAGUUGAGGCCAGGCAGGGUGGCUCAUGCCUGUAAUCUCAGCACUUUGUGGGGGCCGAGGCAGGUAAAUCAUUUGAGCCCAGGAGUUCAAACCAGCCUGGGCAACAUAGUGAAACUGCAUCUCUACAAAAUAUUUUAAAAAUUAGCCAGGGAUGGUGGCAUGUGCCUGUAGAACCAGCUACUCAGGAGGCUGAGGUGGGAGGAUGACUUCAGCCCAGGAGGCAGAGGUUGCAGUGAGCUGAGAUCACACCACUGCACUCCAAUCUGGGCAACAGAGUGAGACCCUGUCUCAAAAAAAGACAGUUGACUUAAAGACUUUGUCUAGCAAAUCCAGUAUCUGUCCUUCCUUAGGGACAAUUUCUGUUUAUUUCACCUGUGAAUGGGUCACACUUUCUUGUUCUUCACAUGCUUUAUAAUUUUUUGUUGAAACUAGAUAUUUUUAAUACCAUAAUAUGAUAACUCUGGAAAUCAGACUCUUCCCCUUCCUCAGUAUUUUGUUUUGUUCCUUGCUCUGGGUUGUAAUUCUUGUUUUUUUAGUGACUAUUCUAAACUAUUUUUGUAAACAUAUUAUUUGUCACAUGUAGUCUCUAAAAUGUCUUUUUCUUUAGCUUAUGGUCAACUAGUGUUUUGACAGAUAUUUCUUUGAACACCAGAAGGAAUAAACAAACAAAUAAAUAAAUAAAUUCUGUGCUUGUCUUUGCAGAUUGGCUCUGUUUUGGGGCACUCCUUUAAUGCCUAGACAGGCUACCACUCUGCGUUAGCCUUGACUUUCUUCUUGUACCCAGCAUAAUUAUCAGCCAUAGAUAAAAUCUUAGAGUCUUCUCAGAACUUUUCUAAGUAUGCACCCUGCCCUAGGCAUGUAUGUGGCUUUCCAAAUUCCCUGGUAUAAGCAGACAUUUUCUUAAUGCCUGAAUUCUUCUAAGAAUCUUUCUCCCCAGCUUUUCUUCCCAGGCAUUCGACAUAUCUAUUUUUUGCCUCCACUAUAAUGUUUUGCCCCAGGUAUUGAUGGGUUAUUCAUUGCCUUUCAGUGUUUAUGAGAAAUGUCCUCUGCAUGGCUAAUUUUCUACCUGAAAGAGAGGUAGUUGAGACAAAGACAAGUGCUUUUCCUCAGUUUUUUAGGGAGCAUCCAGAUAGUUGAAAACAGACAAAUACAAUUCUUUCAGAACCAGUUCUGCUCUAUGCCUGCUGGAACCAGUGACCAUGGUCUCCUACUGAAAAUGUAGACGGCUGUCUUCAAGACUGCUAUCAAGUUGGAGAAAAAAGAUCGGGGAAAGGGCAAUCAAACAUUCUGCAAAGCUCCCCAAUGAUUUUUUUUUAAUUGUGUAUAUCUAAGCUGUACAACAUGACAUUUUGAUAUAUGCAGUGAAAUGGUUACCCUAGUCAUGCAAAUUAACAUAUUCAUUAUCUUGCACUGUUACCCUUUUUGUGCAAGUAUGGUAAGAGUAUCUAAAAUCUACUCUGAGCAAAUGUUCGGUAUACAAUACAAUAAUAUAAGUAUAGCCUUCAUGUUGUAUAUUAGAUUCCUAGACUUAUUUACCCUACAUAUCUGCAACUUUGUACCCUGUGACCUACAUCUCCCCAUUUCCUCUCUGUUCCCUCUCUCCACCUCUGAUAACCACUGCUUUAUACUUUGUUUCUAUGUAUUUGGCUUUUUUUAACUCCUUUUUUUCUUUUGCUUUUUUUUUUUUUUUUUGAGAUAGAGUCUCACUCUGUCACCCAGGCUGGAGUGCAAUGGCAUGAUCUCAGCUCACUGCAACCUCUGCCUCCCAGGUUUAAACAAUCCUCCCCAGCUGGGACUACAGGCAUGUUCCACUCUGCCUGGCUGAUAUUUUUGUAUUUUCAGUAGAGACAGGGUUUCACCAUGUUGGCCAGACUAGAACUCCUAGCAUUUUUAAGUUGCCUCUUUUUUUGACCCAUCAUUUGUUUGGUUGCUAUAAACCUUUGACUAGUUUCUACAGUUCUGACAAAGUUGAUUCUGACAAUGUUUGCUCACUCUGUGUGUGUUCGCAUGAGUGUGCAUGUUUUUUGUGGAGGGAUGGACCCUUGCAGUUAUUUAUUGUGCCAUUUUGACUAAUGUCACUGACCCUCAGACUUUAGGCCAGCAAUUUCAACAAAGUAGUCACCAUUCCCCUGAAAUCCCUCUCCCCUUUGAUGCCACACCUACCUAUACUAUGCCUAUUGCUAAUAUUAGGUGAUCCCCAGCACCUUCUUUCCCUGUUCCUGGGCUACAAGUGCUAUAAUCAUUGGAGAAAGUUAUUAGUGUGGUGCAAAAGUGAUUGCGGAUUUUCCCAUUGAAGGUAAUGGCAAAAUCCGCAAUCACUUUCGCACCAGCCAAUGCAAAACUGGAUGGACUCCAUGAAUGGUGCGUGUCAACCAAGCUUGGCCAAUUCCUCCUCACUGCUUCCACACUCAUUUAUUGAUGACUUGUCAGUUUCCUAACAAAUUCCUCAUAGCAGCUUUUACAUGUCUCAUCCGUCUUCCUCUAGAUUCUAUGAGAUCUACUUCUCUUAGAACAACUUUGAGAAAAACAUAAGCGAAAUAUUCCAACUUCUUCCCCUUUACCCUCUAAAUCUUUUGAGAUCUUUAACCUUAUUCUUUUCAGUCUCAAAAGAAAAGGAGAACCACGUCUACCCAAGACUAACCUCUUCACUUAUGCUCCUAAGCCCACCCUGGCUUCCUCCUCAGAAAUGACACCGUUUUGAAUACUCCCUUUCACCAUAUCUUAAGUUUUUUCUUUUUCUCCCAGCUGCUUCCCUUUGCUCCAAAUUUGCUCAGGACUCUGUUACCUAAAGAGUAACUUCCAUUUGUCCUACCUUCUCAAUAUCCUGACUAUGUUUCUCCUCCCUUCUCUUUAAAUUCUCUUGAGAAAUCAGCCCCUACUCUCUUUCAUACUGCAUUUGCCUCCUGUGGAGCUAACACAGCUUGCUAUAUUCCUGUUAGCUAUAGAUGGGCCUAAGCUAGUCCCUCAGGUUAGAAACCCAAAGUUCCUUGACUUUUCUCUCUUUUUCAGAAUCUGCUUAGUUCUACCUCUCUCCUCUCUUUCCUAAGACACUGCUCUCUUUAUACUUUGCCAAUUUUCAAAAAUACUUCAUGUUUUUUAAUACCUUCCAAACUAACCCUCCACUAAUCAGGUAACCCUUAAAAACUUCUCUAUUCUAAUUCCAAUCUACUUAACAUUCACUGAGUUCCCUGGACCAGGUUAUGGGGAAAUACAAUGCUGACUAAGAUAUUAUUUGAGUUCCCCAAAACACAUCAUACAGUAGAUGAAACUUGUAAACAAAUGUACCCCAAAUGUCUGCUGUCUUGACAUCCUCACCAGUGGAUGGGCAAGACCUCAGCAUCACCUUCAUGUUGCAAGGAGUUCCCCAGUGACUUAUGAGAGUCUCAAAGGAAAGCUUCCCAUGAGUCCCCAAAGCAGCCUACGAGUUGUAGCCAACAUGAGGCAUCUUUCCCAUUCUUAAUCUCCUUUUCUGGUUCUAGUCCCCCACACAGGAUGCCAGCAGAGCCAUUUAGAUGCCCUGCUUAUUCCAAGAACAUCAAUGUCCAUGCCAAGGGUGCUGGUCCCGGAUGCUCCCAAAGCAUCAGUGUUGAUUCCUGGCAGAGCAGAGAAAAGGACCUCCAUGUGCCCUCUGGGCCACACCACAACACCUUGGCCCUGAAGCAGCUCUGCUCCUGUCCAAAGUCUCAUGCAGGGUCUUUUAAACAUUUUCAGUAGCAUCUGACCUUCACUGUCCCUAAGCAUAUUGUCUCAAAUCUAGUUUUGCUUUGGUUUGGUUUUGGGUCUGUGGGGAACUAUUCCUACCAUCUCAUCCAUCCUGUGCUCCUUCUCCCUUUGCUUCACCACAAACUCCUUUCUCCCCUUCCCCAUGUACCAAUGCAAAACCCCCAUAAAUAUAAGAGGCAAACAGAUAUUUUAGCUCAUCCUUGAAGGAUAAAUAGGAGCUUACCAUGUAGGAAAGAUGAAGAAAGGCAUUUUAAGCAGAGGGAAAAGCAGUGCAAAAAAAAAAAAAAAGCAAGGCAUUAUUGGAAGAAUUACAAAUAAUUAAGUAAUGGAGAACUCAUAGCUUUUAUUCAAGACUUUGCUACAGUGUCAUCUCCUGUGAACUGUUCCCUGACAACUCCCAACUCUUCCCAGUUCAUGAUUCUCUAAAUUUUUGCUCCCAUGGAGCACAUAUCUCUAACAAUUCAACAUUUAUUGAGCUAGAAAUUGUGUGCUAAGUUCUAGGAAUAUAGAAAUAAUAAUCAGAAUCCCUGACCUCAAGAUUAUGGAAAAGAAAAGAAAAUAAUCUUGUAAUUAUAACAAAGAGAAAGAACUGCUUGCAAUUGCAUGUAUAACUGCAAUAGUGAUACGAGGGCAAUGCAGAGGCAAGCCUUACACUAGCUCAAUGCCCAACCCACCACAUCAGAACUAACUACUCAUUUACCUGUCAGGCUCCUCUAUCAGAUGAUGGACCCAGAGGACUGACAGUAUCUUAUAUUCCCAGUUUCCAGUCUAGAAACUGGUACAUAAAACAGACCUAAUAAAUAUGCCAUGGUUCCUAAGGUUUUACUAAUUGAAUUAGCAUGGAAGUUAGCAAAUAUUAGAAUAUUUGAACACCAGAAUGAAUAAACAAACAAACAAAUAAAUAAAUUUCUGUGCUUGUCUUUGCAGAUUGGCUCUGUUUUGGGGCACUCCUUUAAUGCCUAGACAGGCUACCACUCUGCCUUAGCCUUGACUUUCUUCUUGUAAGCAGCAUAAAUAGCCAUAGAUAAAAUCUUGUUACAUAAACUAAUUAUUUCAAUCUAUAAAAUCAAUGGAACUUAAACAAGCGUUCCAGGCAAGGGAAGAACAGCUCCUGGUGAGUCCUUAGGCCACUGAGUAAGCCCAGACUCCCUACCAAAAGGAACUGAGCUUUAACAUUCUAGACAGAAAACCUCCAAGAGAAGGGAUGGAGAUAUGUCCAUUCACUCAGUAAAUAUUCAUGGGAUGCUUACUAUGUGCCAGGUGCUGUUCAAGAAUGUUCACAAUAGUAGACAAAACAGACAAAAAUCUUUGUCUCCAUGGAGAUUACAUUCUAGUGGAGAGGUGAGAAAAUAAACAAAAACAAAUAUUUAAAUUAUAAAGUAUACUAGAUGGUAAGUACUAGAUGGUAAAUCCAAAGGCAGCUGGAUGUGCAAGGGUGGAUGGGGGCUGAUGGUGCAAAAAGAGUGGUCACACUUCUUUAAAUUCUCUGAGCAGGAAUGUUUGCAUUAAUGACUUUAUGGAGGCAAAAGAGUGAGCUGCAUGGAUACUUGGAGAAAGUACAUUCCAGACAGAAAGGAUUGCAAAUGCAAAAGCCCUGGCCUGCUCAAGGAAUAGCCAAGGGGGCUGGAGCAAAGUGAACAAGGGGGAGAAUAUAGGAAUUAGGUCAAAGAAAGAGAAAUGGCCAGAUCAUUUUGGUCCUUAUAGACCAUAGACAUGAUUUUGUUUUGCUCUGCUUUUGUUACUGUUUUAACUUUUUAAACUGAAAUACAAAGAGAAAAACUAUACGAAUCUUAAAUGUCAGCUCAAUGAAUUAUCAUAAAAUGAACAAAUCUGUGUAGCCAAAUACAGAUCUAGAGAUAGGACAUUAUCAGUAUUCCAGGAUCCUUCCUUUAUACUCCCUCCUAUUCACCACCUCUCCCUCCUCAAAGGUAACCACUCUCUUGACUUCUGACAGCAUAGAUUUGUCUGUUUAUCAACUUUAAAUAAAUAGAAUCAUAUAUUUGUAUUCUCUGGUAUCUGGACAUUCUGCUCAAAAUGUUGCUUGUGGUAUUCACCCAUGUGAUUCAGAGGAAAGAGGAAUAAAGAUGACAAAUAACAGUGUGUUAAAAUGCUGAUGGGAAAGAUGUUGAUGACAGCAAUGUUCAUGUGCCUGGAACCCAUAUGACAAUUCAUGAAAGAGAGAGGAAGUGCAAGCUCACCCAGGAGCUGAGCACUAGGACUCCAAGAGACAUUUCCUUCCCUAUUCAGCUCCUCCUAUAAGAAAUAAGAAACCCUCAGAAAUGACAACUUUCCAUGCUCAUGGAUUGGAAGAAUCAACAUCGUUAAAAUGGCCAUACCACACAAAGCAAUUUCUAGAUUCAGUGCUAUUCCUAUCAAACUACCAAUGUCAUUCUUCACAGAAUUAGAAAAACCAUUCUAAAAUUCAUAUGGAACCAAAAAAAGAGCCCAAAUAGUCAAAGCAAUUCUAAGCAAAAACAAAAAAUCCAGAGACAUCACACUAUCUGACUUUGAACCAUACCAUAAGACUAUAGUAACCAAAACAGCAUGGUACCGUUACACAAACAGACACAUAGACAACUGGAAGAGAACAAAAAACUCAGAAAUAAAGCCACACCCUUACAACCAUCUGAUUUUUGACAAGGCCAACAAAAGCGAGCAAUGGGGAAAGGACUCCCUGUUCAAUAAAUGGUGCUGGAUAACUGGCUAGCCAUAUGCAGAAGAUUGAAACUGGACCCUUACCUUUAACCAUAUACGAAAAUUAACUCAAGAUGGAUCAAAUAUUUAAAUGUAAAACCUCAAGCUAUAAAAAUCCUAGAAAAAAAUAGGAAAUACCCUUCUUGACACUGGCCUUGGCAAAGAAUUUUUGGCUAGGUCCCCAAAAGCAAUUGCAACAAAAACGAAAAUUGACAAGUGGAACCUAAGUAAACUAUAGAGCUUCUGCACAGCAAAAGAAACUAUCAUUACCGUAAACAGACAUCUUACAGAAUGAGAGAAAAUAUUUGCAAACUAUGUACCCAACAUAAGGUCUAAUAUCCAGAAUCUAUAAGGAGCUUAAACCAAUAAGCAAAAAGACGAAUAACCCCAUUAAAAAAUGGGCAAAGGACAUGAACAGGCACUUCUUAAAUGAAGAUAUACAAGCACUCAGCAAACAUGAAAAAAUGCUCAGCAUCAGUAAUCAUCAGAGAAAUCCAAAUCAAAACCACAAUGAAAUACCAUCUCACACCAGUCAGAAUGGCUAUUAUUAAAAAGUCAAAAAAAAGAACACAAUAGAUGCUGGUUUGGUUUUUGAUAUGGUUUGAUUGUGUCCCCACCCAAAUCUCAUCUUGAACUGUAGAGCUCCCAUUAUUCCCACAUGUCAUGGGAGGGACCUGGUAGGAGGUAAUUGAAUCUGGGGGUAGGUCUUUCCUGUGCUAUUCUCAUGAUAGUGAAUAAGUCUCAUGAGUUCUGAUGGUUUUAUAAAGGGGAGUUCCCCUGCACAUGUUCUCUUUGCCUGCCACCAUGUAAGACGUGACUUUGCUCCUCCUUCACCUUCCACCAUGCUUGUGAGUGCCAUGGCCUCCCCAGCCAUGGGGAACUGUGAGUCAAUUAAACAUCUUUCCUUUAUAAAUUACUAGUCUUGAGUAUGUCUUUAUCAGCAGUGUGAAAAUGGACAAAUAACACUUUUUUGACUUUUUAAUAAUAGCCAUUCUGUCAGAAUGACAGCUGGAAGAGAACAGAAAAUUCAGAAUACACUAAUACACUUUUUUGUAUUUUUGUAUAGCCAUAUGCAGAAGAUUGAAACUGGACCCUUCAUUCUUUCAGAAUGUCUAUUAUUAAAAGUCAAAAAAUAAAAAAAAAACAGGUGCUAGGUCCCACUUGGUGAGGUUGCAGAGAAAAGGAAACAGUUAUACACUGUUAUUGGGAAAUAUAAAUUUUCACUGUGGAAAGCAGUUUGGAGAUUUUUCAAAAAACUUAAAACUGAGCUACCAUUCAACCCAGCAAUCCCAUUACUGGGUAUAUAGCCAAAGGAAAAUAGAUCAUUAUACCAAAAAGACACAUGCACUUGUAUGUUCAUACUAUGCUAUUCAUAAUAGCAAAGACACAGAAUCAACCUAGGUUCCAAUCAAUGAUGGAUUGGAUAAAGAAAAUUUGGUAUAUAUACACCAUGGAAUACUAACCAGCCAUAAAAAAGAAUUAAAUCAUGUCUUUUGCAGUAACACGGGUGGAGCUGGAGGCCAUAAUCCUAGCACACCAACACAGGAACAGAAAACCAAAUACUACAUGCUCUCACUUAUAAGUGGGAGCUAAACACUGAGCACACAUGGACAUAAAUAUGGGAUUAAUAGACGCUGUGGACUACUAGAGGGGGAAGGAAGGGAACAGGUAAUGGGUUGAAUAACUACCUAUUAGUUAUUAUGUCCACUAUCUGGGUGUGAUAUACCCAUGUAACAAAUCUGCACAUGUACCCCCAUAUCUAAAAUAAAAGUUGAAAUUUUUAAGAAAAAGAAGCAAGAGAUCCUGAGAAGGUUGAGGUAAUUGUUAUAGUUAUUCAUUCAUUGACCCACUAGAACAUUUCCACAGACUCUACUAUGUGUCAGACAUGGUGCUGAGUACUGACAUGCAAGGCUAAUUAAGGCGUGGUCAGUUAGACAAACAGGUGAACAAAACUACAAAAUAGUGUAAUAAUUGCUAAGAAUUUGGGAAAGGAUGCUAAGGAAGCAUCUUCUUUAAGAAUCAUUGUGACCAUUUCACCGUUUUUGCUUAAACAUUGAUAGUUCUGAAUAAGUUCACAAGAAUGUGGCCAUCAUGUGUUACUUUGAAAUUAUAUUUAUUAUUUCUAUAUGUAUCCAUUUUGUCUCCUCAAUAACUAAACUAUAAUCUUUCUGAGAGAAUUAAAAAAAAAUCUUCUGGUAUCAUGAAGACAGCACAAAGUCACUGGAGUCAGAAGACCUGGGUUUGAAUCCUGACUCUGCUAUUCUUUAGCUGUGCAACCCUGGGAAAAUUAGUUAACUUUUCUGUAGCUCAGUUCCUUUAUCUAUAAAUGGAAGUAAUAAUAUCCAUCCUGCCUGCCUCACAGACUGUAGUCAGCGUCAAUGAAAUAAUAUAUAAGAAGAACUGACUAUCCUAUAAAUCCCUGAUAUUAGUCCCUGUUACCAGCCUUCUAAGUUGCACAAGCCUACUAUGUUGGACACACAGUAAGUAAUCAGUAAAUAUCAGGCUUUAAUUAUGCUUUAUUAGCAAAGACUUGCAGUUUUUGGAGUCUAUAGUUUCCUGUCCCCCUCAACCUAAUGUCCAAGGACUUCAGAGGCUAGGAUCACAAAGUAUAGUUAUGACCUAGGAGUGACCAGCCAGUGUAGGACCCAGCGUGGACUGGGCCGGUUUCAUCUAGACUAGCUGCCUACUAACCAAGAGUGGCUGACAUUUUGCUGGAGGGAAUGUAGUUUCACAAAGCAGCUUAACCCCAUUGAUGGUGAACGGGAUUCUGGGGGAGUCAGUAACUCUUCCCCUGGAGUUUCCUGCAGGAGAGAAGGUCAACUUCAUCACUUGGCUUUUCAAUGAAACAUCUCUUGCCUUCAUAGUACCCCAUGAAACCAAAAGUCCAGAAAUCCACGUGACUAAUCCGAAACAGGGAAAGCGACUGAACUUCACCCAGUCCUACUCCCUGCAACUCAGCAACCUGAAGAUGGAAGACACAGGCUCUUACAGAGCCCAGAUAUCCACAAAGACCUCUGCAAAGCUGUCCAGUUACACUCUGAGGAUAUUAAGACAACUGAGGAACAUACAAGUUACCAAUCACAGUCAGCUAUUUCAGAAUAUGACCUGUGAGCUCCAUCUGACUUGCUCUGUGGAGGAUGCAGAUGACAAUGUCUCAUUCAGAUGGGAGGCCUUGGGAAACACACUUUCAAGUCAGCCAAACCUCACUGUCUCCUGGGACCCCAGGAUUUCCAGUGAACAGGACUACACCUGCAUAGCAGAGAAUGCUGUCAGUAAUUUAUCCUUCUCUGUCUCUGCCCAGAAGCUUUGCGAAGAUGUUAAAAUUCAAUAUACAGAUACCAAAAUGAUUCUGUUUAUGGUUUCUGGGAUAUGCAUAGUCUUCGGUUUCAUCAUACUGCUGUUACUUGUUUUGAGGAAAAGAAGAGAUUCCCUAUCUUUGUCUACUCAGCGAACACAGGGCCCCGCAGAGUCCGCAAGGAACCUAGAGUAUGUUUCAGUGUCUCCAACGAACAACACUGUGUAUGCUUCAGUCACUCAUUCAAACAGGGAAACAGAAAUCUGGACACCUAGAGAAAAUGAUACUAUCACAAUUUACUCCACAAUUAAUCAUUCCAAAGAGAGUAAACCCACUUUUUCCAGGGCAACUGCCCUUGACAAUGUCGUGUAAGUUGCUGAAAGGCCUCAGAGGAAUUCGGGAAUGACACGUCUUCUGAUCCCAUGAGACAGAACAAAGAACAGGAAGCUUGGUUCCUGUUGUUCCUGGCAACAGAAUUUGAAUAUCUAGGAUAGGAUGAUCACCUCCAGUCCUUCGGACUUAAACCUGCCUACCUGAGUCAAACACCUAAGGAUAACAUCAUUUCCAGCAUGUGGUUCAAAUAAUAUUUUCCAAUCCACUUCAGGCCAAAACAUGCUAAAGAUAACACACCAGCACAUUGACUCUCUCUUUGAUAACUAAGCAAAUGGAAUUAUGGUUGACAGAGAGUUUAUGAUCCAGAAGACAACCACUUCUCUCCUUUUAGAAAGCAGCAGGAUUGACUUAUUGAGAAAUAAUGCAGUGUGUUGGUUACAUGUGUAGUCUCUGGAGUUGGAUGGGCCCAUCCUGAUACAAGUUGAGCAUCCCUUGUCUGAAAUGCUUGGGAUUAGAAAUGUUUCAGAUUUCAAUUUUUUUUCAGAUUUUGGAAUAUUUGCAUUAUAUUUAGCGGUUGAGUAUCCAAAUCCAAAAAUCCAAAAUUCAAAAUGCUCCAAUAAGCAUUUCCCUUGAGUUUCAUUGAUGUCGAUGCAGUGCUCAAAAUCUCAGAUUUUGGAGCAUUUUGGAUAUUGGAUUUUUGGAUUUGGGAUGCUCAACUUGUACAAUGUUUAUUAGACACAUCUCCUGGGACAUACUGCCUAACCUUUUGGAGCCUUAGUCUCCCAGACUGAAAAAGGAAGAGGAUGGUAUUACAUCAGCUCCAUUGUUUGAGCCAAGAAUCUAAGUCAUCCCUGACUCCAGUGUCUUUGUCACCAGGCCCUUUGGACUCUACCUCAGAAAUAUUUCUUGGACCUUCCACUUCUCCUCCAACUCCUUGACCACCAUCCUGUAUCCAACCAUCACCACCUCUAACCUGAAUCCUACCUUAAGAUCAGAACAGUUGUCCUCACUUUUGUUCUUGUCCCUCUCCAACCCACUCUCCACAAGAUGGCCAGAGUAAUGUUUUUAAUAUAAAUUGGAUCCUUCAGUUUCCUGCUUAAAACCCUGCAGGUUUCCCAAUGCACUCAGAAAGAAAUCCAGUUUCCAUGGCCCUGGAUGGUCUGGCCCACCUCCAGCCUCAGCUAGCAUUACCCUUCUGACACUCUCUAUGUAGCCUCCCUGAUCUUCUUUCAGCUCCUCUAUUAAAGGAAAAGUUCUUUAUGUUAAUUAUUUACAUCUUCCUGCAGGCCCUUCCUCUGCCUGCUGGGGUCCUCCUAUUCUUUAGGUUUAAUUUUAAAUAUGUCACCUCCUAAGAGAAACCUUCCCAGACCACUCUUUCUAAAAUGAAUCUUCUAGGCUGGGCAUGGUGGCUCACACCUGUAAUCCCUGUACUUUGGGAGGCCAAGGGGGGAGAUCACUUGAGGUCAGGAGUUCAAGACCAGCCUGGCCAACUUGGUGAAACCCCGUCUUUACUAAAAAUACAAAAAAAUUAGCCAGGCGUGGUGGUGCACCCCUAAAAUCCCAGCUACUUGAGAGACUGAGGCAGGAGAAUCGCUUGAACCCAGGAGGUGGAGGUUCCAGUGAGCCAAAAUCAUGCCAAUGUAUUCCAGUCUGGGUGACAGAGUGAGACUCUGUCUCAAAAAAUAAAUAAAUAAAAUAAAAUGAAAUAGA